AAUCACCGCCCAGAGGGAAGGAGGUCGGCAGUGUGAGGAGCUGCUAUGGUGCUGAGUUUCCUGGUAGAGCCGGCCGAGCUGAGGCGGUCGCGGCCAUGAAGAUUUCUGGGCAGAGACUGAUUCCUGAUGUCAUGGAAUGCUAACAUGUGAAUGUUCAUGUGGGGGAGUGGUACUAAGGAUCAAGUAUACUGUUAAAAGAAAACAAAAACCCAAGCAUGAGGAAGGGAUUCUGAAAACAUAUUAGAUUAUACACACACAGAAGCAAAGACAGCUGAACCUUGAGGCCAUUUGAAAAUCCUGGCACUGUGCCAGAAAGAGAGCUGGGCUGCUGCUCUUGCAAAGAAACAGAACACCUUUCCUCUUGCUUUUGUUGACUGUAAUGAUGUUUCAUGGGCUUAUAUUGUUUGACUCUGACUGAGGAACCUGAGAGAGUCCUUAUAACCUUAUUGGCUGGAAACUGUCAUUCCUACUCUUACGCAGAUUAUUUAGGCGGGUGCCACGUCUAUGUGGGCUUCGUGCUGUGGGCUGCUGAAUGAAGUCAUGGGAACUGGAGCUGUCAGGGGCCAGCAGUCAGCAUUUGCAGGAGCCACCGGUCCAUUCAGAUUUACACCAAACCCUGAGUUUUCCACCUACCCACCAGCAGCUACGGAAGGGCCCAACAUAGUUUGUAAAGCCUGUGGGCUUUCAUUUUCAGUCUUUAGAAAGAAGCAUGUUUGCUGUGACUGCAAGAAGGAUUUUUGCUCCGUUUGUUCAGUCUUACAAGAAAAUCUCCGUAGAUGUUCUACUUGUCACUUAUUACAAGAGACAGCAUUUCAGCGCCCUCAGUUAAUGCGACUGAAGGUGAAGGACCUGCGGCAGUAUCUCAUUCUGAGAAAUAUACCCAUAGAUACUUGUCGUGAGAAAGAAGACUUGGUGGAUCUAGUACUGUGCCAUCAUGGACUAGGCUCUGAGGACGACAUGGACACAAGCAGUCUGAAUUCUUCAAGGUCCCAGACUUCUAGCUUUUUUACACGUUCGUUUUUUUCAAACUAUACAGCCCCCUCUGCUACUAUGUCUUCGUUUCAGGGAGAGCUUAUGGAUGGAGACCAAACAUCCAGAUCUGGAGUGCCGGCACAGGUACAAAGUGAAAUCACUUCAGCAAACACAGAAGAUGAUGAUGACGACGAUGAUGAGGAUGAUGAUGAUGAAGAAGAAAACGCAGAGGAUCGGAACCCCGGGCUCUCCAAGGAGAGAGUGAGAGCUUCACUGUCUGACUUGUCAAGCCUUGAUGAUGUGGAAGGAAUGAGCGUGCGCCAGCUGAAGGAAAUUCUGGCUCGGAAUUUUGUCAACUAUUCUGGCUGUUGUGAAAAAUGGGAACUGGUAGAGAAAGUAAACCGGUUAUACAAAGAGAAUGAAGAAAACCAAAAGUCCUAUGGCGAGCGGCUGCAGCUGCAGGAUGAGGAAGACGACAGCCUGUGUCGCAUCUGCAUGGAUGCCGUCAUCGACUGUGUCCUACUGGAGUGUGGGCACAUGGUUACCUGCACCAAGUGCGGCAAGCGCAUGAGUGAGUGUCCCAUCUGCCGGCAGUAUGUGGUGCGAGCCGUGCACGUGUUCAAGUCCUGAAACAGGCUCCCCUCACCAGGACAGUCACCCCCAAACUUGACCCCCAACAUUUCAAUGCACAGAAGGGACUGGAAAGUUAUGUUCAAAGGCUGAAGCUAUUUUAAAACAUUAUUUUGACUACUAAGUGGGGACAGAAAGAUCCAUCCUGAGUUGUGGAAACAUUGGUCCAUGCCGUGAGCCUGUCUGCCUGUGGACACGUGAGCUUCCCGGGCUCAGCUGGGCUUUAUCACACAUCCCGUGAACACUCAUUGAAGUCAGCCUGUUUGCGCCAUGUGGGCAUCAGCCACUGCUGUCUUGGGAGGACACUUAUCCUGUUCUCUUAUUUCCCCUUCAUCCUAUUUUUAACUUAAACUGCUCAGAUGUUUGAAACUUCUGUCCUCUUUGGAUGAGAUCAGUGUCCACAAGUGGCCGACAUGGAACAUGCUGAGCAGUGGCUCCUCUGAAUGUUCACUUUAUUAGUCAUGUAUAUUUUAAAUGCUAACAUUUGAUGAAUGUAAGUUUCCACAUUGUUGCUGUUUCUGCAUUUAAACAUAAUUGGGAACAACUGACAUUCUCUAGUCGACUGCCAGGGCCUUAGACUCCACAUGUCCAUUUUUGUUCAGGUAUAGCUUUUUAUAGCAAGGGCUGCAUCUAGCUUCUUUUAUUAGAAGUGUGUGUGCUAAAUUCCUUAUUAAUGUGUAAUCAGUUUACAUUGUUUUGUAUAGUGAAGGUGUAUUUUCAGUGCUACCCGCUAGCUGAUUUUAACUUUAGGAAUAAAAUUAGUUUUAAAAGC